ACACCUCCCACCAUGCUGGCACUGAGGUUAUCUAAGAGUUGACAGCCCCAUCUAAAGCCUUGAAUGAAUUAAGUCUUUUUUAGCUAAAAAAUGAACAAAACCUGAGAUGCAUGAGUGUCCUUACCAAAAGGAAGUCCUUGUUUCUAGGACAGGUCUGUCUUCGGGCCUGUGGGUCCAUAGAAUCAUCACAGAAAAAAUGAUUUCAGGAGGUCUCCCCCGCUUUCUGCUCCCAAGGCCGACUCUGACUGAGCCUCGGAGGAGAGAAGGAAGCCAUUUCUGGGAGGCCAAAACGUCCGUCUUCCAGGCUCUUGCUGUAAGUCAGCCCACUUUUACAGAUGAGGAACCAAGACCCAGGGAAGAUGGGAAGGCAGAGAAAAUCCAUCAAGUUGUACCCUACCCACCCUUUGGUGACUUUUCCAAGAAGCUGGGCUAAGUUCCAGGAGAAAGCUCUGCUAGAGUGCAAUGGCACCAUCUCGGCUCAUCGCAACCUCCGCCUUCCAGGUUCAAGCGAUUCUCCUGCCUCAGCCUCCUGAAUAGCUGUGAUUACAGGCAUGCACCACUACACCUGGCUAAUUUUGUAUUUUUAGUAGAGACGGGAUUCCUCCUUGUUGGUCAGGCUGGUCUCGAACUCCUGACCUCAGGUGAUCUGCCUGCCUCGGCCUCCCAAUGUGCUGGGAUCACAGGUGUGAACCACCGCACCUGGCCAGAGAUGCAGAUUUGAUGGUCAUCCUCAGAUGCAACAGAUGAAACCCUGGGAAUGAAUGGAAUUACACAGCCAAGGUUGAUACAUGGUAAAACAAAGCAGCUGAGGAGAAUUUUCAAGGGAUACCAAUGUUCAGGGGUGUGUAGCAGAGGAGCCAAACAUGGACAGCAAGAAACCACAGAAAGGAGAGGGCAGAGUAGCAAAAGCCCAGGAAACUGUAAAGGAGGAGGUGUCCAUAGUGUAAAAUGGUGCAGACCUGAGACAAGGCAUUCAAUCUGGCAGCCAUCAGCUCAUUUGAUGGCUUUUGAGAAGUCUGUUUCAGUAGGGAGGAGGAGAAGAAAGCCAAAAUGCAGAGCGAAUGACAGGUGAAGUGCAAGAAGUCAAUAGAGGCCACUCUCUGGAGAAGUUUAGCAAUAAAGAGGAGAAGUUAGGGCAGCUGACUAUAGAAAAGGUGUGGACAAAGAAAGGGUUGGUUUAGCAUUGUUUAUGGAUUAUCAUUGUUUAUGGUUUGUCAUUGUUUUCUUUUUUAAUGUGGAGGAGACUUGAGAAUGACUUUAAACUGAGGAAGGAUCAAAGAAAAGGGAAGAAAAUGAAGAUAUAGAGCCAAAAAGAAAAAUCUUAAGGGAUAAUUGAUGGAGCUUGGUCCUAGCAGAGGUAGAAGGGCUUAGAUGAGAAUGGGAUCUAGUUAACCCUGGACAAGAGUUCUUGCGAAUCAGUAGAGCAAGAAGAGAAGAAAAUACAUGGGUGUCCUAGAGGAAAAGAUGAGAGCUUAGAAUCUUUUUGUAGCCCCAUGACACUUAUUACACAUUUAAUAAUUUUGCUCUCUAUAUCUGUGAAAAGAGUAAAUAGUAAACCACGAAUGAUAAUCAUUGCUCUCAAAGUAAGUCACACCAAAAUUUCUAUGCACCUUGCCCCAAAAAAAGAUGUUUCCCCUAGUGUAGCAAGAAAGUGAACCUAAUGUUCAUAAUAUUCCUACAUGAUAUAACUUUGUGUCCCUCAAAAAAUAUAUGGUGACUUUCUGUUUAAUUUUGCUAUUAAAUAUCUGAAUGGGACCUGCCCAGUACAUCUAAUUCAAAUCAAAGAAAUUUUGACAGGACUUUACCAAAACCAAGCAUGCCUGCUCAAAGAAAGCUCAUGAAAAGGGUUAUGAAACAAUUAAUCGACCACAGGUAAAGCCCUUCCAUCUGUUCCACCUACCCCACCUUCAGUGUGAAAGGCCUCGGUCUCUUCAGCCAUCUGGAGAAAAAAAGAAGAAAAAGCUAAAAAUAGUGGGCUGCAACCAAAAUGAAAGUAUCUAAAUGUUGGUAACAGUGUUUGAAGAGGAAAGGGCAUGUUCCUUUGAGUGGUUUCCAAUCUAGGUCUCAUGGCCUGAAAUGUCUGCCUAACUUCUGAUUUAAAGAGAACAGAAAUAAAUACUGGCUCUUAGAAAGAAGGUGCCUUGAUUGGGGUGAGCACAUAAAACAAUGGAAAAAGUGACAAAAGCUGCUUUUGUCUUACCUUUUGUUUUCUCUUUUCAUUAUUAAACUGUAAAAGUAAUGCCUGUCUGCUUAAGAAAUAAAUUCAAGUUACAGACAUAUAUAAAGUAGGGAUCAACCACCUCCCAUCCCUACUGCCACUCUAGCACCUCUUCCCACAUUUUGAUGUGAGGAAUUUAUUGCUUUACCUUUCCAAAUUUGCAUGUAUGUGUGUUUAUAAAAAUGGGAUCUUACUAUUCUCCAACUUGACUUUUUUUCUUUUCACUAUAUACUAUGGAAAUUUUUCCAUGUCCGUGCACAUGGAUUCUUCCUUGUUCUUUUGACGGCUACAGAAAACUACUCUUUUAUUGCUCCAUAAUUCAUUUAGUCAGUCCCCCAUAAGAGGAUCAUUUAAACUAUCUCAAGACUUUUUACCACAGAAAAAGCUGCUGUAAACAUCUCUGUACAUACAUCUUUGUGGUCUUGUUGUUUCUUAAAUAAAUUCUUAGAAGUGAAGGCAAAUUGCUGGCUUAAAGGGUGUGUACCUUUUCAGUUUUGAUGACAAUUUCCAGACUGUCCUCCAAAAAAUGUCAUACUAGCUUAUCCUCCUAUCAACAGUUUUUAAGAGUGCCUUUUUCCUCAUGCCCCAGACACUACUGAGUGUUAAUACUCUUUAAAUAUUUCCUUGCUUAUAGAUAAAGGUACUUUCUUUGAGCAGAAGGUUAGGGAUAUUAAGGGAACUUCCCUUCUAGAAAAGUAGCAGGAGGAUCAUAUGUUAAGAUUUAAGAGAAGGGAGGGAGAUGAACGUGUCAGGACUAGGAAUGCUUUAGGAGAUAGCCACUUGGGUGGAGUGGAGCAGGAGCUGACCCACAAUGUCCAGGCAUCUAAAAAGCCCAGAGAAAAUUGGGGAAAAAAUGUCAAAAAGUUUUUAUGAAGUCAAUAUAGUUAGUUAUGUGACUUCUCUAGUUUGGGAACAAGAACAAAAAAAAAAUGAGAGACAGGGUCACCCAGGCUGGAGUGCAGUGGUGUGAUCAUGGCUCACUUCAGCCUUCACUUCCUAGGCUCAAGCCAUCCUCCCGCGUCAGCCUCCCAAAGUGUUGGGAUUACAAGUGUGAGCCACCGCACCUGGCUGGGAAAAAUUUAAGGUUGGAAUCCAUCAGUAUAUUAAAAUUGAGUGGUCUGGUGAGAAAUAGAAACUUCUCAUAGUUAAAUGAUUGCACAAAGGUUUGACUUGAGACCAAAGAGAAAUGAGUCAAAGAGAAGGACUGAUGGGCUAGAAGAAAAUAGAAGUUUCGAAGAUCACAGCUGGCCAGGCACGGUGGCUCACUCUUCUAAUCCCAGCACUUUGGGAGGCCGAGGCGGGCGGAUCAUGAGGUCAGGAGUUUGAGACCAGCCUGGCCAACACAGUGAAACCCUGUCUCUACUAAAAGUACAAAACUGAGCUGGGCGUGGUGGCAGGUGCCUGUAAUCCCAGCUACUCAGGAGGCUGAUGCAGGAGAAUCGCUUGAACCCAGGAGGCGGAGGUUGCAGUGAGCCGAGAUCAUGCCACUGCACUCCAGCCUGGGUGACAAAACUAGACUCCAUCUCAAAAAAAAAAAAAAAAAAAUCACAGCUAAAUCACAAUCAAGUUAGAGGCAAGGUUUAAGGGGAGUGAGAGAGUUAGAGCAGUGGUCAGAGAGUUGGUGAUGAUUAGCGAGAAGCAUUUCCGAGUUCAAAAUUUCAACAAGGCGUGGAACAGCUGCUGGCUAUGAUGGGGUGUGGGGAGCAGACAGGUCCUGAAGUGAAUUGGAGCUGAAGGUUUCUGAAGAACAGCAGGUAAAGCCAUGACAAAGGGGUGCUAUGUGGGUCAUGUAUCAGGGAUGGCAAGAUAGGGUGGAGCCAUUCUGCAGGUCACCUGCAGAAAUCCCAAGGCCUGAUUGAGUAUGCUUGAAUGAGUGAAUGUUCUGGAUGCUGAAGGGUUGAUGGAGAAGAGGGAGCAGCAGAGCAAGAAACAAGAGCUUCAUUGAGGGAGGGCUGGUUGAGCGGCUGGCUUCACUCAAGGGUCAGGAGGUGACUGUGAAGGACGCACAGACUACCAGCCACCCAUAGGUACAGGUGUUGGGAGGGAGAGGGUGGAGAGAAGGAAGCUUCCUCUUUGGUAAGGAGUGUUUGAGGAAAAAGCUGAUGAUCUCAGGACAUCAAGAAAUAUAUUGUGAAUCCCACAAGGCAGUCACUGGAAGCUGGAGAGGAAAAGUGUUGAUUAGGAUUUCUAUCAGGCAAUUUGGGGACACUGAAAUGAUUGAAUGUGAAUCAAGGGAAUUAGGAAUCAGGGCAUCCGAGAAUGGAUAAAAGGAAGGAAUGGUCCACAUGGAGCUUCCCAGUGAAGGUGUACUGGUGCCUCUCCAUGGUGGUGCUGCGGGGAGGAGGUGUGAGAGUGAGACCAUCAAGUCCCUCCAUUCUGCAGGGAGUGGGGAGACUGUGUAUCUGGCUGGUAGCCUCUGCAUACUCAUGCAUGUCCUUCCAUCGACUCACUACAUGACCUUGUAAAAGUUACCUACAUUCACUUAGCCUCCAUUCUCUCUUCACAAAUAAGAGUAAUCAUAGUAUGCAUCUCAUGAGGCUGUUUGAGGAUUAAACAUAGCAUGUUAGACAUGAAACAUGUAUUACUGGAACACAGUAAAUAUGCAAUCAAUUAAACUAUAAUUACUCACAUUGUAGAAGGUUUUAAAAUAUAUAUCCAUUUUGAAGGGGAAAGUUUUCAAAAUAUUGUAAAUUCUAAGUAACAAAUACAAUGGGCACAUGGAAAAAUCUCUCAACACACAAAUAGAACCUUCUUAUGUGGACACGACAGCGAUCCUAGUAAAAACAACUAUCUCCAUGGUUUUCACGGCUUCUCUUACACAAAAUCAAGUAUAGAAAUUCAUACAUUAAAUCUCUUAAAAUGCAAAUUUUUUCUGCCUUAUAUAUGCAGAUAUUUAAGUUCAUGUUGUCUUCUGGUUUAUAUUCAGUCUCACUAUUUUAAAAUAAAACCAAAUUAUAUCACAUAAGAACAACUGGGAACCAUUUAUCUUCAAUUCUAUACACGAAAAGUAUCAGUUCUGUGUAUGUUAGCUGUUCAAAGUUAUUCUCCACAGUCUUUUUUGUGGAUGAUUUAAUGAAGACAUUCUUACCACGUUUCUGCUAUCCCUGUACUUGGGUUAGUUUUGCAGGCUGACCGGGUGGAAGUCAGAUAAAUUCCCUCCAUUCCUAGAAAGACAUUCUCCAAUUAGCUUAACACUAGUCCCUUAGAUUGGUGUCUUAGCUUCAAUGGUAGCACUAGACCAGAUAUGUAACUUUUCUUUAUAUCACCCUGGGUUUUAGUGUGUUCAGUUAUUUUUUUCCCUGCCCAGGUCAUUCAUUUCCUGCUUAAUAUUUUUAGCAAAGCAGUGACAUUUUGGCAAUAUUGACUUCUAAAAGUAAAAGCUCAUCUAACAUUUAAUCUCUUAGCGUUUGUAAGGAGUCCACAUGCUGGGCUGUUUCAGGUAUUGGUGCCCGUGUUUGCUAUGUUCCCUCUGUCCUUUCUGCCUUGCUUCUCCCAGGCUAACAUUUGCUAAUCCCUGAAGGUUCAAUUCAGGGAUUUUCCUCAAAGCUUUCCCUGAAACCCUAAAUUGAGCUAAGUGCCCCUUGCCUGGUUUCCUAAAAGGUGAUCACAUUAUGUUGACAUGACAUGAUCCUCUAAUGGGUCCGUCUGUCCUGCUGGAUGGUUAGCAUCCUUGAGAGCAGGGACCUUACUUCAUCUUUGUUCUCCCAACAACCGAUAGACACUUUAGACACAGGGCCGAUGGCCUAUAAAAAUGUUUGAAAUCAGAAAUACACAGUUGCACCUGAACAACAUUGGUUUGAACUGUGUAGGUCUACUUAUACAUGGAUAUUUUUCAAUUAAUAUAUUGGAAAAAUUUUUGGAGAUUUUUGACUAUUUGAAAAAACUCACGGAAAUAUCAAAAAAUUCGGAUUUUAAUUAAUGCAUAAAAUAUAUGUAAAGGUUGGUCUAUUUUAUAAUUCACUACCCUAAAAUAUACACAAAUCUAUUACAAAAAUAUAAAAUUUAUCAAAACUUAUGAACAGAAACACUUAGAGACCACAUGGCACCAUUCACAGCAGAGAGAAAUGUAAACAAACAUAAAGAUGCAGUAUUAAAUCAUAACUGCAUACAAUUAACUGUAGUACACUUUGUACUAAUGUAAUAAUUUUGUAGCCACCUCUUGUUGCUAGUGCAAUGAGCUCAAGUGUUUCAAGUAUCAGCUUAAAAUAGCUAUGAGGCUAAUUAUCUCCACCUGAGCAGUUCAUCUCUCCAGUAAAUUAUGUGUCAUAGUAAAAAAGUGAUUUCCAGCAGUUCUUGCAUAUUUUGUGUGUAGCGCAAUACUGUAAGCCUUAAAUAACAUCAUGGGAUCCAUACAAAGUGUCACUAAUGAUGCUGGAAGUACUCCCAGUAAGCAAAGUCAUGAUAUUACAAGAAAAAGUUGAAUUACUUGAUAUGUACCAUAGAUUUAGGUCUGCAGCUGCAGCUGCCCUCCAGCAUAAGGACCAUUGUAAAAAAGAAGAAAAGGAAAUUCAUGAAGGCGUCACUGCAUCUACUCAAGCUGCUGCAAAAACCUUGUACUUUUGGUGAACUACCUUUUUAUCUUGUAUUAAAAAUGCAGCUUUUAUGUGGGUAUAGGAUUGCUCUAAGAAAGGCAUCUCUAAUAUAGUUUGAGAAAAAGUGAAGUCAUAUAUGAAAACUUAAAGAAAAAGGAAGAUGAAGGAUCUAAAGCCAGAGAAUUUAGUGCCAGCAAAGGAUGGGUCGAUAAUUUUAGAAAGAGGUUUGGCUUUAAAAAUAUCUUAGUUGGCAGCUUCUGCCAACUAAGAGGCAGUAGGUGAGUUUCAAGACACCACUAAGAAAAGUAUUGAAGAGAAAGGAUAGCUGCCUAAACAGGUUUUUAAUGCAGAUGAAAAUGCCCCAUUCUGGGAAAAAAGAUACCACAAAGGACAUUUAUUCAUAAAGAAGAGAAAUGAGCACCAAAAUGUAAUAGGAAAGGAUUAUCUAACUCCAAUGUUUUGUGCAAAUGCAGUGAGGUUUAUGAUCAGGUCUGCUCUUGUCUAUAAAGCUGCAAUCUCUGAGCCUUGAAGGAAAAAGGUGAACACCAGCUGCCAAUCUUUUGGUUGUACAAGAAGACCUGGACAACAAGCACCCUUAUUCUGGAUUAGUUCCAUCAAUGCUUUUGUCCAUGAAGUCAGGAGGUACUUUUCCAGUAAGGGACUGACUUUUAAAGUUUUCUUUUUAUAUUGGACAAUGCCCCUGGCUACCCAAAACCCCAUGAGUUCCAUGUCAAAGGUGUUGAAGUGGUCUACUUGCCCCCAAACACAAUGUCUAUAAUUCAGCCUCUAGAUCGGGGGUCAUAAGGACCUUUAAGGCUCAUUGCACAUGGUUCUUUAUGGAAAGGAUUGUCAAUGCUGUGGAGGAGAACCCCAGCGGAGACAACAUCAUGGAGGUCUGGAAAGAUUACACACCACUGCAGAUGUCAUCUUUGCUACAGGAAAAGCCAUGAAAGCCAUCAACCCUGAAACAAUAGCUGGAGAAAACUGUGUCUGGAUGUUGUGCAUCAGCCAAACAAGGAAACCAUGAAAGAGAUUGUAGAUAUGCAAAAUAAGAACAGGGGCAAAGGGUUUCAAGGUGUGAAUCUUGGAGAAAGAUUCAAGAGCUAAUAGACACCACACCAGAGGAAUUAGCUGAACACAAGUUGAUGGAGAUAAGUGCUUCCGAACCAGUGCCAAAUAAUGAGAAAGAUGUAGAAGUAGUGCCAGAAAACACAUUGACAUUAGACAAUCUGGAAGAAUGGUUUCAAUUAUUCAAGACUGAUUUUGACUUCUUUUAUGACAUGGACCCUUCUAUUAUGCAGGCACUGAAACAUGCAAAUGGCGGAAGAAGGACUGGUACCACGUAGAAACAUUUUUAGAUAAACAAAAAAGAAAAAGUCAGACAGAAAUUAUGCAUUUCCAUAAAGUUACACCGAGUGUGCCUUUCUCUCCUGACUCCCCUUCCACCUCCUCCAACUCUUUCUCCUCUGCCACCCGAGACAGCAAGACCAACCUCUCCUCUUCCUCCUCCUCCUCAACCUAUUCAAAAUGAAGACUUUUAUAUUAUCCACUUCCACUUAAUGAAUAGUAAAUAUAUUUUCUCUUCCUUAUGAUUUUCUAGUAUUUUCUUUUCUCUAGCUUACUUUAUGGAAAUAAUAUAGUAUAUAAUACAUAUAAUGCAUAAUGUAUGCUCAUGAACUAUUUAUGUUAUUGGUAAGGCUUCCAGUCAACAGCAGUCUAUUAGUAGUUCAGUUUUGGGGGAGUCAAAAGUUAUAUGUGGAUUUUUGACUGUGCAUGGGGUCAGCACCAUUAUCCCUUGUGUUGUUCAAGGAGCAACUGUAAAUGCUUGGGCUCAAAAUAUUAAAAGAAACCACAAAAUAUAAAUUAGUAAUUGUUUUAUGGAAUGUCUUCAAAGUGUAGCAUUAAGUCAAAGUAGAACUCAAACAGUAGUUAUAUAAAAACAUAAGGGUUAAGUCAUGAGAACUAAAUAAUUCAUUCUCAAAAACUCCUAAAAGUUAUAUAAAUCACCUCAAAGUUACAUUUAACAUGGGAAACAGGGAUAGCUGAAUAUGUCUGCUGCCUUAUGAUAUGCUUUCCAAGAGAGGGCAUGUCCAGGGCCAAAAGCAACCCACAAACACAGUAUCUGGAACCCAGUAGGAACUCACAAAUGUUUGUUGAGAUGUUCCUGUUUAUCUCCAAUUUAAUUCUGCAAGCAUAGCUCAGAGCUUCUUAUAGCCCAGCCAUACUAUGUUAUUAUAUAAUAAAUAUUUCUUCCUUCAAGGAGCUUGCAACAUAGUAGUUGGGAAGACAAACUCAUAUAAGCUGGCUAAAAAUGACAUUUCCGUUUGAGUUCACUUUAUUUUUCAUAUUUUAUUUAUCCAUCCCAUUGAGAAAACUUCCAGUCAUGAACACAGCUAUUCAUGACACAGCUAUUCAGCUCUUCCAAUAGGACUACACAGCCCCAGCUUUGUAGGCAAAACUUUCUGAGCAAAUUUAAUUUUUUGUUUACAUUUUCUAUGAUGAAAUGCAAUUGGUGAACACCCUUACAUUGCCAGAAGUCCAUGGAAACAUUUAGUGAAGACCACAGAUCUAGGAAGACCCACAUUUCUGAAUAAGACACUCUUAAAGGUGCUCCAUCCUUGUAUAAGCUGUCAGUAUAUCUCUUUUUGUAGUUUGCCACUUGUAAUAAUAAUAAAUGUACAUCUCUGGACACUUCUACUGCAGCACCUGAUGAAAAUUCUGGUUCCCUGUCCAAGACAACUCUCAAUUUCACAAUCAUCACACUCAUCCCCAACUUUUCCACACUCCUGUUAAAACCUAGCCCAAAUUCCACUGCCUUCUGGAAGACUUUUCUGAAUCUCUCCUCUCCAGCCUCAACAGAAGUGAACUAUCUCGCACCCUCUCUGAACUACCCUACUACUUACUGUCUACUUUGAAAUUAUUCUGCAAGCUUGAAUUCUCCCUUCACUUGAUUAUAAGGCCAUUUUUGAAAGAGACCAAUCCCAUCUUGUUCAUUAUUCCCUUCCCCAUUGUGUCUUGCGAGUAUCCAGAUUUCCAUUAACAGCUGCUGAAUAUACAGACUGAGCUUGUGGGUUUAACUGAAAUGUAUAUGCAUAAGGGAGUAUGGAAAGAGGAGCUGGUGCGUAUCAUCAUCUUUACAAUCAAUUUUUCUUGUACUUUACAAGAAGGUAUUCCCCACAACCAAUUCUUAAAAUUUUUUGAGGUAGACUUCUCAUUUUGAUGGUUUCGGUGUUUGUUCCCUUUGGGGUGUUGUUAAUGCAUUGAGAUUAUCAGUGAAACUAAUCUAUCAUUUGGGCUAAGUAAUUGCCAACAUCCACACAUUCUUAGAGGGAGUUGUAUUUUAUGGUGAACCACUUCCUUGCUUGACCUGCUUUAAUGCAUGUGAUAGUGAUUUCACUAAUCUAGUUUGUCAGCACUCUCCAAUACCCUGCUGGUCACUAGGGUGUUUUGAAAGCAACUGAAAAUAGCCUCUUGCCUACUUCAGGCCUACUCAAAUGCAUAUCUCCUGUAAAGAGCCCUGUAAUCUGGGCCCUUCUCUUCUAUAAGGUCUUGGCUACUUUCUCAGCAGCCAAGGUGGGGCAAGAUGGGGAAGUUGAAGAGAACUUGUAUGGUAGAACUUCAUGCAAGAAGCCAUGCUGCAAAGAUCCUGUCUUCUUAAGAAUAAUGUCCUAAAAUAAUUUCCCCUAUUUUCCACCUACUACCAGUUCAAUAUUUAUCAAACUUUUCUCUUUCCCAUAUAACCUUUCAGAUUUUUACAUUUUCUGUGUAUCACCUAUUUUUUUUUUACUUAAUCAUUUUCUUCAUUUCCUCUUUCUACUUAAGUAAAGCCUCACCUUAGUCCCCCUGCAUCCCCCCAAAAUUUAUAGUGCAGGGGCAGCUGGGGCUUUCUGAGUCCCUCCACUUCUUCCCUCAGAUUUUCCCCUCAGAUUUUUUCCUCAGACUCACUAUCAUGGCCACAGAACCUUGCACACAACAGGGGUUCUGUAAAUAGUGGCAGAAUGAGUGAAUCUGUUGGCAUCCCUGAGGAGGCCAUGAUCAGCUUUCCAUUCCUCCUUUUGCCAAGUCUAGGUUGCAAACACCCUGAAACUGGUGGUCUUAGUAUGAUGACUGGGAACUUAUAAAGUCAUAAGUCUCAUUUCAUAAUAAUAUAAAAAGAAUUUAUCUUCAUUUUAUUUAUGUUGAACUCUGCUAAAAGGUAAAAAAUGGACUUGUGUGCCUCCCUCCAAAUUUACACACACACAUACACUCACACAUACACACAUUUUAAAAAACUGUCACAGCAAUUAAAAUAAAUAAAAACAGAGCCUAAGAAGAUCACUAGUAAAGUAGGAUGGAGCUGUUCUCCCUCACGGCUCGAAUUGUUUGCUUUGGUGACCAACCCGCACUAGUAAACAACCUGAAGUACAAGUUCAGCCUUUUCAUGAGCCAAAUUCAUCACUUUUGAGACUAAAAUUCAUGUUCAGAUUUGCUGACACUAUUUAGACAGCUUAUGUAACAACACUCAACUCUGUUGGGUAGAUUGGCUAAUGGUGAUUAACCUCCUUGGUAUAGAAGAUUUUAGAUUAAAGCAGAAUUUUAAAUUACAAUAACUAGCUGAUGGAGUUUUGCAGAACAAAUUUUAAAAUCCCCAAGCCACAAAUGUAAUAUUUGCAUUAUACACACGCUCCUUUCAUUCCCUUGAAUUGAUAACACUUCGCAAUCACAAGAUUUGGCCUGGGAGAAAAUAAACGAGCUUUUCAGCAGUGCAAGCUGAUGACCAACUUUGUUUACUGAUCAGUCAUAAAAGUUUUUAUGAACUUCAUCUCGCACCCACAACACCUUGUAAAGUGACCCUCUCACUAUGUGAACACAACGAAUGUCUACAGAGGAAAGAACCACGUAUUAUGAGGAUUAACUACUGGAAUGGAAUGUGUCUAUUAAUAGCUCAUAGUAGGCACUAAAUAAUGGCAACCAAAUUCAACAACACUCACUAAACAGAAAUGGGGAGGUGGGAUGGUAAAGGGGAAGUUUAACUGAGCUUGGAAGGGGUUAAUAUUCAGGGUUGAGAGAAUCUGCCCUUAGGAAUCUUUCAAGAAGACAGGGAUCCUGCCCAAAUGCCAUUGCAGUGCCAAGGGUAGGGAGCCUAGCCAAAGCUGAAGUUGGGCAUACCCACGCCACUGCCUUCAGGCCAUCAUUCCGUGCAUUGGAAUGCUCCAGGUGACACACAGGAGAACCUUGUUUACUGUUCUUGACCCAAGGCUUGAGAUCCUUCUGUGGGCAAAUGCCUGCACAUCACCUCUGUAUCAUGUGAGUGAAGGACUCUGAGUCCCUGGUAUUUGCAAUAAUCGAUCUCAUCCUACACUUGUCCUUCCAAGCCAGUGUUUCUAAGAGUGGUCCUGAUCUGUGAUCACUCCUGGAACAUCGGUUAAAAAGUGCAGAUCCCAAGGACCCAAGCUAGACUUGUGAAUCAGAAUUUCUGGAGAUAAGGCCCAGGAAUUUGUUCAACAAGCUUCCAUAGUAGUUCCAGGCAUAUGGAACCUUUUGAAAUUCACUGCUCUCGGAGAAAACCCAUGCUUUUUGCAUUUUUUUUAAAUGGAAAAAUGUUGCUAGAGACUUUUAGCUGGAAAUAUAAGAGAAGAUAAUAACAACACAGUAAUAAUAAUGGGCGGAGUCAUGGGGAGGGGUCGUUUGAAGCUCUAUUUGAGAACCUGCUGGCAUUGGUGUUGUUGGCCUGUCUCAGCCACCCUGAUGCUCAGGUAGGAACUCCUGAAAAAAAAAAAUGUCUGGGCCGCGCCCUAUGAGACCAUUGAAAGGUCUGGGAUGUCCAUUCAUCCUUGGGGUCACCUAUGCCACAGGAAGUUCUGGACAAGAACUUCCCAACAAUCCAUAAGCGGACGCCACGAGGCGCGAAGCGCGUUGGUGGCCACACGCAACUCCAGGCAGCCCAACCCUCCCGCUACCUUCUGCAACUGCAGUCAGCUCCCAAAAGUGAACUGGCACAAAAAGGUGGGACUUCCGGCCCUGGAAGCCAAUGCGCAUGUGGCAGUCAACCGGUUACGCAAUACUUCCUGUCGCGUGAUCCUGAGGACCAAUGAAAAUGCAUAAUUGCAGUCCACGUGCCUCGGUUUCCGUUAGCAACCAGAGGCUUCUAAACAACCUACCCUCCUUCCCCAUUUUCUGUGGUCCAACUACCCUCGGCGAUCCCAGGCUUGGCGGGGCACCGCCUGGCCUCUCCCGUUCCUUUAGGCUGCCGCCGCUGCCUGCCGCCAUGGCAGAGUUGGGCCUAAAUGAGCACCAUCAAAAUGAAGUUAUUAAUUAUAUGCGUUUUGCUCGUUCAAAGAGAGGCUUGAGACUCAAAACUGUAGAUUCCUGCUUCCAAGACCUCAAGGAGAGCAGGCUGGUGGAGGACACCUUCACCAUAGAUGAAGUCUCUGAAGUCCUCAAUGGAUUACAAGCUGUGGUUCAUAGUGAGGUGGAAUCUGAGCUCAUCAACACUGCCUAUACCAAUGUGUUACUUCUGCGACAGCUGUUUGCACAAGCUGAGAAGUGGUAUCUUAAGCUACAGACAGACAUCUCUGAACUUGAAAACCGAGAAUUAUUAGAACAAGUUGCAGAAUUUGAAAAAGCAGAGAUUACAUCUUCAAACAAAAAGCCCAUCUUAGAUGUCACAAAGCCAAAACUUGCUCCACUUAAUGAAGGUGGAACAGCAGAACUCCUAAACAAGGAAAUUUUAAGACUUCAAGAAGAGAAUGAGAAAUUGAAGUCAAGGUUGAAGACCAUUGAAAUACAGGCUACAAAUGCACUGGAUGAAAAGUCAAAACUAGAAAAAGCACUGCAAGAUUUACAGCUUGAUCAAGGAAAUCAAAAGGAUUUUAUAAAGGCCCAAGACUUAAGUAACUUAGAAAACACUGUCGCUGCCUUAAAGAGUGAGUUUCAGAAGACACUUAAUGACAAGACAGAAAACCAGAAGUCACUGGAGGAGAAUCUGGCGACAGCCAAGCACGAUCUACUCAGGGUUCAGGAGCAGCUGCACAUGGCUGAAAAGGAAUUAGAAAAGAAAUUUCAGCAAACAGCAGCUUAUCGAAACAUGAAAGAGAUUCUUACCAAGAAGAAUGACCAAAUCAAAGAUCUGAGGAAAAGACUGGCACAAUAUGAACCUGAAGAUUAAAACUGAAGAUUUCCUCUGGAAGCUACCACAUGCAAACAUACAAGCAGUCUCACCUCAGGCAUGUAUUUUGAAAAGCAUUUUGUCAUAUCCCCUCUCCUUAUUUUUCUAAUAUUUAGACUUUGAAUAUUUAGAACUAGAGUUCCUAUUUUCAGCUAGUUGAAAACAGAGAAAACCUAGUGAUUCUGUCUGGUCAUCCCACACACCUCUCUACUGAGUGCUCCAGAGUCUUAGCUCACAUGCACUGAGAAUUCUUUACAGCAAAGAAGAGAUUUUUAGAGUGGGAAGAAGAGGCUUAUCCUUCUGCAUUAGUAUAAAGAGUCUGUAUUUUUAAUAAAUGUUAAAUAAGCUAACAAUGUUUGUACUUAUGCAUUCCCCAUGGGUAAAAAUAAAUAAUAGCAUUGUUAAAGAUAGUUAUUACCAAAAAAAGAGAGUUAUUACAAAUAAAUAUGUCUCUUUAUUUUUAAAAAUGAAAUCUUAAUUCAUUUACUCUAUUUGAUGAUAAACUAUAAAUUCAUUGAAAAUGUGAAUUCUAUUAUGGGUAGCCUUUUUACCAAUUAUAAGGAAAAUUUACAGCAGUGAACAUGAACAUUCACUUAGCUUCCUCAGUCUCUCCAUCUUAAAGAUCAUUUAUCAGAGGAGGUUCAGCAUUUUUUGCAGCAUAACUUUUCAUGAGUCUGUAUUACUAAUGGAUAAGUCAAAUCCAUCCUGCACUUCUACAGUUUAGAAAGUAUCUGGACUCAGAAUAAAUGUAAUAUUUAUACUUGUUUCCAGAAUGUUAUUUUACAUUUUAUGUUCAAUAAGAACACUUUUUAAAAGACGUAUAUUCAACAUAAAAUCAGCUAUCAGACUUCAGAUUAGACUUUAUUUAUGUGGGUCUAUAAUAAUUGUAUUUUCAAGAGGUUUUCACUAUAUUUGUAUUGGCCUGGUUUUCUCAGACGAUUUUGGACAAAUCAUUAGAAACUGGGCAUCAUAUCCACAGUUAUGUAAGGCAGUGAUAUACUAUAAGGAUAAACAAAGUCAAGUCCAUAAAGCAAUAAUCCCUCAGAAGGAAAGUCCUUACUUUUCACAUAUUAAUAUUUAGUAAUUUUUCCUGCUUCUAAAAGUGAGAGUAUCACACCCUAAAUGAACACUGUCUACUAAGAGACAUCAUUCCAUUUCCACAAAUGAAGAUUUUAUUCCAAGAAACGAGUUUACUGAUUGGAGCAUAGGGCUUGUUGUUAUUUUUAUUCAAGCUUUUAGUAAUAGCCUUGAAUUUAUUAUUUUUCUUAUAGGCUUUUUGUUAAAAUAGUGAAGGAACAAAUGUUAAAGGGUAAGAUAAUUUCCCUGCAAAAGGACACAGAAGGCAGUCUUAAGAAGAUGAAUGGAUGAGAGAAGGGAGAGAAUAAAAUGCAAUAACGAGCCAGCAUUUACUAUGUAUUUUCUCCUCACCUGUCUCUCCAUAUUUAGGUCACUUACCAGUUUCUGUGCCCUUUUGGAGCUUUUGUUGAGGGCUUCAUUCUCACCCUGUAUUUCUUUAGCCCUAAAUUGACACUCUCUCCAAAAAUCCAUUCCAUUGUCUGUGGACCAAGAUGUUCUAUGUAAUUCAGAAGCAGAACUCUUGGCUAAAGGGCUAGUGUGGCCUUCAGAAACCAUUCAAUUAUUUUCUCCCUACACCUUUGUCAGUUUGAAACCAGUGAGGAAAAAAGGUAUGUUGAUAAGAAACCUAUAUUGCUAGGUAGAAUUUGUACUUGUUUUCUUGGUAGCAGUUUUGAAAUAUUCUGUACAGUACGUUCCUAUUGUUUAAUAAUAAAUUCAAAAAUAUUUCUAAAACCUUAAAACCAACUAUGCCAAGCAUUAAGAUAAACAAAUAUGAUGUUCUUUGACGUAAAUCAACGUGAUGAUUCUUUCACAUGUAAACACAUUUUAGUGUUUCUGGUUUGUCAUUUUUGUUGUUGUUGUUGUUGUUGUUAUUUACUCUAUACCCUUUAGCAAAAUACAGUUUUAAAUUUUUAUUGUUUUUAGUAGUUUCCCAACUUUAAGACUUAUCUAAUUUAACUGAGAAAGAAAGCCUUUUUCAUAUAUAUAUAUAUUGGAUUUCUAAGGAUGGUGGUUUGAGCCUUGAUUAGACUUUUGAUGUGCUAAGCCAGACAGGCAGUCUGUACAUUGAUGGCCAUCACAAUGCAGCUUUGGUUUAAUUUAAUUCAGGCCUGCUGCUGAGUUAUGCACAGACUUUUUGUUGACCAAAAUAAAAUAUAAAGGGUUUUCUUCUGUUUGACAUUUGUGUUCAUUUUUUCUCUUUAUGUAUUACAUUUUAACCUAUAUUAAAUAAAUGUUUAAAUGAUAAUUUGCUUAUGUCUUAUAAAACUCAGCAUAAGAAAAAUACUGCCCUACCUUGACUGUGUAAUCUUAUUUGAUAAAGCCUUUGCUAUUCAUUAUUUCCAUUCUGAUUAACUGAAAGAGAUUUAUAGAGAUGCUCAAAUUUUAAGCCCUUGGUGCUUUUAGAUAUAUAUUGGUUGCAAAAGUUUGGCAUUAAUGAUUUCCCUCUGCUUAUGUGUAAAUGCCUAUGUUCCAAAGCUUUGCCACUAGAUAUUCAAAUCAUAAAUUGUCAUGUAAGCCAGUCUUCCAGAAAGAAAAGCUAUUUCAGCAAAAUGAUAUUUCACAUUUAGACAAAACAGUAGUAUUUAGACAAUAAUAUUUUGACAAAACCAUUUUCAAAACUGCUUAGGAAAAAGGGGAAAUAUUAUACUUAAAGGUAAUGACCUCUGUCUUGAAUAGAGGUGAGUGGGUUGGUGACAACUGGUUUGGAGGCUUUUGUGGGGGACUGUGGUGUCUUUUGGAUUGUGUCAUCAGCUCCUUCAUCAAGUAAGCGUGUAGCUGUUAUUGCCUAUUGUAAAACAUGAAUUGAUGUGAACAGUACUCAAUCUCUUACAUUAUAUGAAGUAUAACUUCCUCUCUUUUUUGCCUAUAAUACAUCCUUUAACUUUUACAGAUUAAAAAACCACUGUUAGACAAAGCAAAA